AGAGUCCUGAGCUGAACCAAGAAGGAGGAGGGGGUCGGGCCUCCGAGGAAGGCCUAGCCGCUGCUGCUGCCAGGAAUUCCAGGUUGGAGGGGCGGCAACCUCCUGCCAGCCUUCAGGCCACUCUCCUGUGCCUGCCAGAAGAGACAGAGCUUGAGGAGAGCUUGAGGAGAGCAGGAAAGGUGGGACAUUGCUGCUGCUGCUCACUCAGUUCCACAGGGCGGCAGUAAGUCUUCAGCAUCAGGCAUUUUGGGGUGACUCAGUAAAUGGUAGAUCUUGCUACCAGUGGAACAGCCACUAAGGAUUCUGCAGUGAGAGCAGAGGGCCAGCUAAGUGGUACUCUCCCAGAGACUGUCUGACUCACGCCACCCCCUCCACCUUGGACACAGGACGCUGUGGUUUCUGAGCCAGCAGCCUCCCCCGUUGCCCCUCUGGAUCCACUGCUUAAAUACGGACGAGGACAGGGCCCUGUCUCCUCAGCUUCAGGCACCACCACUGACCUGGGACAGUGAAUCGACAAUGCCGUCUUCUGUCUCGUGGGGCAUCCUCCUGCUGGCAGGCCUGUGCUGCCUGGUCCCUGUCUCCCUGGCUGAGGAUCCCCAGGGAGAUGCUGCCCAGAAGACAGAUACAUCCCACCAUGAUCAGGAUCACCCAACCUUCAACAAGAUCACCCCCAACCUGGCUGAGUUCGCCUUCAGCCUAUACCGCCAGCUGGCACACCAGUCCAACAGCACCAAUAUCUUCUUCUCCCCAGUGAGCAUCGCUACAGCCUUUGCAAUGCUCUCCCUGGGGACCAAGGCUGACACUCACGAUGAAAUCCUGGAGGGCCUGAAUUUCAACCUCACGGAGAUUCCGGAGGCUCAGAUCCAUGAAGGCUUCCAGGAACUCCUCCGUACCCUCAACCAGCCAGACAGCCAGCUCCAGCUGACCACCGGCAAUGGCCUGUUCCUCAGCGAGGGCCUGAAGCUAGUGGAUAAGUUUUUGGAGGAUGUUAAAAAGUUGUACCACUCAGAAGCCUUCACUGUCAACUUCGGGGACACCGAAGAGGCCAAGAAACAGAUCAACGAUUACGUGGAGAAGGGUACUCAAGGGAAAAUUGUGGAUUUGGUCAAGGAGCUUGACAGAGACACAGUUUUUGCUCUGGUGAAUUACAUCUUCUUUAAAGGCAAAUGGGAGAGACCCUUUGAAGUCAAGGACACCGAGGAAGAGGACUUCCACGUGGACCAGGUGACCACCGUGAAGGUGCCUAUGAUGAAGCGUUUAGGCAUGUUUAACAUCCAGCACUGUAAGAAGCUGUCCAGCUGGGUGCUGCUGAUGAAAUACCUGGGCAAUGCCACCGCCAUCUUCUUCCUGCCUGAUGAGGGGAAACUACAGCACCUGGAAAAUGAACUCACCCACGAUAUCAUCACCAAGUUCCUGGAAAAUGAAGACAGAAGGUCUGCCAGCUUACAUUUACCCAAACUGUCCAUUACUGGAACCUAUGAUCUGAAGAGCGUCCUGGGUCAACUGGGCAUCACUAAGGUCUUCAGCAAUGGGGCUGACCUCUCCGGGGUCACAGAGGAGGCACCCCUGAAGCUCUCCAAGGCCGUGCAUAAGGCUGUGCUGACCAUCGACGAGAAAGGGACUGAAGCUGCUGGGGCCAUGUUUUUAGAGGCCAUACCCAUGUCUAUCCCCCCCGAGGUCAAGUUCAACAAACCCUUUGUCUUCUUAAUGAUUGAACAAAAUACCAAGUCUCCCCUCUUCAUGGGAAAAGUGGUGAAUCCCACCCAAAAAUAACUGCCUCUCGCUCCUCAACCCCUCCCCUCCAUCCCUGGCCCCCUCCCUGGAUGACAUUAAAGAAGGGUUGAGCUGGUCCCUGCCUGCAUGUGACUGUAAAUCCCUCCCAUGUUUUCUCUGAGUCUCCCUUUGCCUGCUGAGGCUGUAUGUGGGCUCCAGGUAACAGUGCUGUCUUCGGGCCCCCUGAACUGUGUUCAUGGAGCAUCUGGCUGGGUAGGCACAUGCUGGGCUUGAAUCCAGGGGGGACUGAAUCCUCAGCUUACGGACCUGGGCCCAUCUGUUUCUGGAGGGCUCCAGUCUUCCUUGUCCUGUCUUGGAGUCCCCAAGAAGGAAUCACAGGGGAGGAACCAGAUACCAGCCAUGACCCCAGGCUCCACCAAGCAUCUUCAUGUCCCCCUGCUCAUCCCCCACUCCCCCCCACCCAGAGUUGCUCAUCCUGCCAGGGCUGGCUGUGCCCACCCCAAGGCUGCCCUCCUGGGGGCCCCAGAACUGCCUGAUCGUGCCGUGGCCCAGUUUUGUGGCAUCUGCAGCAACACAAGAGAGAGGACAAUGUCCUCCUCUUGACCCGCUGUCACCUAACCAGACUCGGGCCCUGCACCUCUCAGGCACUUCUGGAAAAUGACUGAGGCAGAUUCUUCCUGAAGCCCAUUCUCCAUGGGGCAACAAGGACACCUAUUCUGUCCUUGUCCUUCCAUCGCUGCCCCAGAAAGCCUCACAUAUCUCCGUUUAGAAUCAGGUCCCUUCUCCCCAGAUGAAGAGGAGGGUCUCUGCUUUGUUUUCUCUAUCUCCUCCUCAGACUUGACCAGGCCCAGCAGGCCCCAGAAGACCAUUACCCUAUAUCCCUUCUCCUCCCUAGUCACAUGGCCAUAGGCCUGCUGAUGGCUCAGGAAGGCCAUUGCAAGGACUCCUCAGCUAUGGGAGAGGAAGCACAUCACCCAUUGACCCCCGCAACCCCUCCCUUUCCUCCUCUGAGUCCCGACUGGGGCCACAUGCAGCCUGACUUCUUUGUGCCUGUUGCUGUCCCUGCAGUCUUCAGAGGGCCACCGCAGCUCCAGUGCCACGGCAGGAGGCUGUUCCUGAAUAGCCCCUGUGGUAAGGGCCAGGAGAGUCCUUCCAUCCUCCAAGGCCCUGCUAAAGGACACAGCAGCCAGGAAGUCCCCUGGGCCCCUAGCUGAAGGACAGCCUGCUCCCUCCGUCUCUACCAGGAAUGGCCUUGUCCUAUGGAAGGCACUGCCCCAUCCCAAACUAAUCUAGGAAUCACUGUCUAACCACUCACUGUCAUGAAUGUGUACUUAAAGGAUGAGGUUGAGUCAUACCAAAUAGUGAUUUCGAUAGUUCAAAAUGGUGAAAUUAGCAAUUCUACAUGAUUCAGUCUAAUCAAUGGAUACCGACUGUUUCCCACACAAGUCUCCUGUUCUCUUAAGCUUACUCACUGACAGCCUUUCACUCUCCACAAAUACAUUAAAGAUAUGGCCAUCACCAAGCCCCCUAGGAUGACACCAGACCUGAGAGUCUGAAGACCUGGAUCCAAGUUCUGACUUUUCCCCCUGACAGCUGUGUGACCUUCGUGAAGUCGCCAAACCUCUCUGAGCCCCAGUCAUUGCUAGUAAGACCUGCCUUUGAGUUGGUAUGAUGUUCAAGUUAGAUAACAAAAUGUUUAUACCCAUUAGAACAGAGAAUAAAUAGAACUACAUUUCUUGCA